AGUGGCCUCCGAGGUUCUGGCGGCCGGCAGUGGCGACCGGCGCAGGGAAUCGCGCAGGGUUGCGGCUGAGGUCAGACCAGCGAGAGACAGAGACCCGCAGACAUUUAGUCCAGAGACUGUAGCAAAGGAGGGGGACGAGGGGCCAGAGCCGGAAUUUCGGGGGAGGACUUGGGAGCGCGGCGACCAGAGUCGCUUGCUGGCACUUGCGAGGGCGAAUGCAGGGGCUUGGCCGAGAUGACCUUGGACCAGAGCUCCCUUCCGGCCUGCAGAGAUGAGCUUGGGGCUUAGCCGAGUAAGGAGUGAGCGGCUUUUCAGCCUCAGUGCUGCGGCAGAGGCGGAUGGAGGAUGAACUGGAGCCGUCCUUACGGCCUCGGACGCAGAUUCAGGGCAGGAUCCUGCUCCUGACCAUCUGCGCUGCCGGCAUUGGUGGGACUUUUCAGUUUGGCUAUAACCUCUCUAUCAUCAAUGCCCCGACCUUGCACAUUCAGGAAUUCACCAAUGAGACAUGGCAGGCGCGUACUGGAGAGCCACUGCCCGAUCACCUAGUCCUGCUUAUGUGGUCCCUCAUCGUGUCUCUGUAUCCCCUGGGAGGCCUCUUUGGAGCACUGCUUGCAGGUCCCUUGGCCAUCACGCUGGGAAGGAAGAAGUCCCUCCUGGUGAAUAACAUCUUUGUGGUGUCAGCAGCAAUCCUGUUUGGAUUCAGCCGCAAAGCAGGCUCCUUUGAGAUGAUCAUGCUGGGAAGACUGCUCGUGGGAGUCAAUGCAGGUGUGAGCAUGAACAUCCAGCCCAUGUACCUGGGGGAGAGCGCCCCUAAGGAGCUCCGAGGAGCUGUGGCCAUGAGCUCAGCCAUCUUUACGGCUCUGGGGAUCGUGAUGGGACAGGUGGUCGGACUCAGGGAGCUCCUAGGUGGCCCUCAGGCCUGGCCCCUGCUGCUGGCCAGCUGCCUGGUGCCCGGGGCGCUCCAGCUCGCCUCCCUGCCUCUGCUCCCUGAAAGCCCGCGCUACCUCCUCAUUGACUGUGGAGACACCGAGGCCUGCCUGGCAGCACUACGGCGGCUCCGGGGCUCCGGGGACUUGGCAGGGGAGCUGGAGGAGCUGGAGGAGGAGCGCGCUGCCUGCCAGGGCUGCCGUGCCCGGCGCCCAUGGGAGCUGUUCCAGCAUCGGGCCCUGAGGAGACAGGUGACAAGCCUCGUGGUUCUGGGCAGUGCCAUGGAGCUCUGCGGGAAUGACUCGGUGUACGCCUACGCCUCCUCCGUGUUCCGGAAGGCAGGAGUGCCGGAAGCGAAGAUCCAGUACGCGAUCAUCGGGACUGGGAGCUGCGAGCUGCUCACGGCGGUUGUUAGUGUAGCUGGGGUGGAUGAGGGCUGGGGGGUCCAGGCCGGGCUGACUUCCACCUCACCCCCGCCCCGUCCACGGCAGAGCUCCUUCCCCUGGACACUCUACCUGGCCAUGGCCUGCAUCUUUGCCUUCAUCCUCAGCUUUGGCAUUGGCCCUGCCGGAGUGACGGGGAUCCUGGCCACAGAGCUGUUUGACCAGAUGGCCAGGCCUGCUGCCUGCAUGGUCUGCGGGGCGCUCAUGUGGAUCAUGCUCAUCCUGGUCGGCCUGGGAUUUCCCUUUAUCAUGGUCUUGGGGUCUUUUUUAAUCCGCAGGAGGCCUUGUCCCACUUCCUCUAUGUCCCUUUCCUUGGUGUCUGUGUCUGUGGGGCCAUCUACACUGGCCUGUUCCUUCCUGAGACCAAAGGCAAGACCUUCCAAGAGAUCUCCAAGGAAUUACACAGACUCAACUUCCCCAGGCGGGCCCAGGGCCCCACGUGGAGGAGCCUGGAGGUUAUCCAGUCAACAGAACUCUAGUCCCAAAGGGGUGGCCAGAGCCAAAGCCAGCUACUGUCCUGUCCUCUGCUUCCUGCCAGGGCCCUGGUCCUCACUCCCUCCUGCAUUCCUCAUUUAAGGAGUGUUUAUUGAGCACCCUUUGUGUGCAGACAUGGCUCCAGGUGCUUAGCAAUCAAUGGUGAGCGUGGUAUUCCAGGCUAAAGGUAAUUAACUGACAGAAAAUCAGUAACAACAUAAUUACAGGCUGGUUGUGGCAGCUCAUGACUGUAAUCCCAGCACUUUGGGAGGCCAAGGUGGGAGGAUCAAUUGAGGCCAGAGUUUGAAACCAGCCUAGGUAACAUAGUGAGACCCCCUAUCUCUACAAAAAAUUUUAAACAUUAGCUGGGCAUGGUGGUAUGUGCUAACAGCUCUAGCUACUCAGGAGGCUGAGGCAGCAGGAUCACUUGAGUCCAAGAGUUCAAGGUAGCAGUAAGCUACAAUCACACCACUGCAUGCCAGACUGGGUGACAGAGGGAGACUUCAUCUCUUUAAAACAUAAUAAUAAUAAUUACAGACUCAGGAAAUGCAGUGAAAGAAAAAUACAGGUUGGCCAGGUGAGGUGGCUGAUGCCUGUAAUCCCAGCACUUUGGGAGGCCAAGAUGGGAAGAUUGCUUUGAGACCAGAAGUUUGAGACCAGCCUGGGCCACAUAGUAAGAUCCUGUUUCUACCAAAAAAAAAAAAAAAAAAAAUUAGCUGGGUGUGGUGGUACAUGCCUGUGGUCCCAGCUACUCAGGAGGCUGAAAUGGGAGGAUCACUUGAGCCUGGGAGGUCGAGGCUGCAGUGAGUCCUAAUUGAGCCACUGCACUCCAGCCUGGACAACAGAAAGAGACCAUGUUUCAAAAAAAAUAAAUACAGGUUGUAGUGGGUAUGGGUAUGCAUACCAGGAGGCCCGACCUCGUCUGAGAGGGGAGUGGUCAGAAAAGAAUUUUCUGAGGAAUUGAUGUUUUUAAUCAACUUUAUUGAGGUAUAAUUUAUACAUAACCAACUGCAUCCAUUUUAAGUAUAUAUUUGGCGAGUUUUGAGUUCUAAGUAUAGUUUUGGUGAGUGUAUACACUUGGGAAACACCACCGUGAUCAAGAUGGAACCUUUACCCUACCCCAAGGCACCCACAUGCCCAUUUGCUAUCAGUAACCCACCCCAGUCCCAGACCUGGGGAACCACUGACCUGCUUUCUGCCUCAAUUGGUCAGAUUUGCCUUUUUUCAGAAUCUGAAGUCAUUCCGUACUGUAUGUACACAUUUGUGUC